AGACCCGGAAGCGGACGGCGUGGAGUGACUAUCCCACCGCCGCGGGAUUGACUUCUAAAGACUCUUGGUAUGUGAGGAAGAAACCUGGAAGAGGAAGAGGAAAGCAAAGGAGUCAGGGAUGGCUCUUCCUCAGGGUCUAUUGACAUUCAGGGAUGUGGCCAUAGAAUUCUCUCAGGAGGAGUGGAAAUGCCUGGACCCUGCUCAGAGGACUCUAUACAGGGACGUGAUGCUGGAGAAUUAUAGGAACCUGGUCUCCCUGGAGUUGUCAGGGGAGUGUCCAUUGGCAGCACCUGCCUCCUGAGUGUCUCCCAGGCCAUCACCAUCAGCCCCAGGAGCUCAGGUGGGCAGAGCUUAAAGGGAACGCCCCCAAGCACGCUGGCUCCUGUGUGUUCCUCAGCUGGCUCCUCCCUGGUCAAUAUCAUUGUUCUCAUGCACGUGACCGGCAAGUGGAGCAACAAAAAUACCACGAAGACAAAAGAUCUGGGAUACUGUUCUGCUGCUGAUCACGAGGGCACCAGAGAGUCGCUGACGCGGCACUGCUGUCCUUCCCUGAUGUGAUCUGCCUGGGGCUCAUGCUCUGGGGCAGCAGCUCCAUCGUUUGCAUCCUGCACAGGCACAAGCGGCGGGUCCAGCACAUUCAUAGGACCAGCGUGUCCCCCACAUCCUCCCCUGAGUCCGGAGCUACCAAAACCAUCCUCCUGGAGCAGGAAAGGACAAGGAGUCCCCGAAGCUGACACUGAGUUCAUGGGGUUGAGCUGACAGCGGCCAACAGGCUGUGAUGGGAUCUCACUCUGUCGGCCAGGCUGGAAUGCAAUGGUGCCAACUUGGCUCAGUGCAACCUCCCCACCCCGGGCUCCAACAAUCCUCCCAUCUCAGCCUCUGAAGUAGCUGGGACUACAGGCGUUAUCUCCUGUCCGGGGAAGAGGUGGGCCUCUCUCCGUCGUGGGAGGAGCUCUGAACUUCUCCUUCAUCCAGGGAUGGGCCCCAGGGACCCACCAGUGGGGCUGGGAGAAGCCCCCCUCAGCAGGAAGACAGAGGUGCCUGGGUGGCCGAGGCCUGGAAGGUCUGCACCAUGGUGCACAGAGGCCCCGGAGCUGGGUGGAACAGUUUAAUCCUGAAACCAUCCCCCCAUCUGUGGAAAAACUGCCUUCCACUAAACCAGUCCCUGGUGCCAAAAACACUGGGAACCGCUAAUCUAGACAGUUCUCUGCUAAGGAAGCACGUGGUUGAGAAGCAUCAGAAUCGUUCCCACGGACCAUGCUCCGGAGUCUCAGCAGGCUCCUGCAGUGUGUUUAUCCGUGCAUCAUGAAGGACCCUCAUACGGCUGACGUGCCUUGGCUGAUGCGAAUAACACUGCAGCAAGCGUGGCAGUGCAGAUAGCUCUUGGAAAUACCCAUUUCCUUCAGACGCAUACUCAGAGAGUAUUGCCCGGGCUGUGAGUGCAGUCUCAUGAUCUUGGGUCACUGCAACCUCUGUUUCCUGGGUUCAAGUGAUUCUUGUGCCUCAGCAUCCCACGUAGCUGAGAUUACAGGAUUGACUUCUAAAGACUCUUGGUACGUGAGGAAGAAACCCGGAAGAGGAAGAGGAGAGCAAAGGAGUCAGGGAUGGCUUUUUCUCAGGGUCUAUUGACAUUCAGGGAUGUGGCCAUAGAAUUCUCUCAGGAGGAGUGGAAAUGCCUGGACCCUGCUCAGAGGACUCUAUACAGGGACGUGAUGCUGGAGAAUUAUAGGAACCUGGUCUCCCUGGAUAUCUCUUCCAAAUGCACGAUGAAGGAGUUCUUGUCAACAGCGCAAGGCAACAGAGAAGUGUUCCAUGCAGGGACAUUGCAAAUACAUGAAAGUCAUCACAAUGGAGAUUUUUGCUACCAGGAUGUUGAUAAAGAUAUUCAUGACUAUGAAUUUCAAUGGCAAGAAGAUGAAAGAAAUGGCCAUGAAGCACCCAUGACAAAAAUCAAAAAGUUGACAGGUAUUACAGAACGAUAUGAUCAAAGUCAUGCUAGAAACAAGCCUAUUAAAGAUCAGCUUGGAUCAAGCUUUCAUUCGCAUCUGCCUGAAAUGCACAUAUUUCAGACCGAAGAGAAAAUUGAUAAUCAAGUUGUGAAGUCUGUCCACGAUGCUUCCUUGGUUUCAACAGCCCAAAGAAUUUCUUGUAGGCCCAAAACCCAUAUAUCUAAUAACCAUGGGAAUAAUUUCUGGAAUUCUUCAUUACUCACACAAAAACAGGAAGUACACAUGAGAGAAAAAUCUUUCCAAUGUAAUGAGAGUGGCAAAGCCUUUAAUUACAGCUCACUCUUAAGGAAACAUCAGAUAAUCCAUUUAGCAGACAAAUAUAAAUGUGAUGUAUGUGGCAAGCUCUUUAAUCAGAAGCGAAACCUAGCAUGCCAUCGUAGAUGUCACACUGGUGAGAAUCCUUACAAGUGUAAUGAGUGUGGCAAGACCUUCAGUCAGACGUCAUCCCUUACAUGCCAUCGUAGACUUCAUACUGGAGAGAAACCUUACAAAUGUGAAGAAUGUGACAAAGCUUUCCAUUUCAAAUCAAUACUUGAAAGACAUAGGAUAAUUCAUACUGAAGAGAAACCAUAUAAGUGUAAUGAGUGUGGCAAGACCUUUAGGCAGAAGUCAAUCCUUACACGCCAUCAUCGACUUCAUACUGGAGAGAAACCUUACAAGUGUAAUGAGUGUGGCAAGACCUUUAGUCACAAGUCAUCCCUUACAUGCCAUCAUAGACUUCAUACUGGAGAGAAACCCUACAAAUGUAAUGAGUGUGGCAAGACCUUUAGUCACAAGUCAUCCCUUACAUGCCAUCGUAGACUUCAUACUGGAGAGAAACCUUACAAAUGUGAAGAAUGUGACAAAGCUUACAGUUUCAGAUCAAAUUUUGAAAUACAUCGGAAAAUUCAUACUGAAGACAAUGCUUACAAGUGUAAUGAGUGUGGAAAGACCUUUAGCCGGACAUCAUCCCUUACAUGCCAUCGUAGACGUCAUACUGGAGAGCAACCUUACAAAUGUGAAGAAUGUGACAAAGCUUUCCGUUUCAAAUCAAACCUUGAAAGACAUAGGAGAAUUCAUACUGGAGAGAAACCAUACAAGUGUAAUGAGUGUGGCAAGACCUUUAGUCGGAAGUCAUACCUCACAUGCCAUCAUAGACUUCAUACUGGAGAGAAAGCUUACAAGUGUAAUGAGUGCGGCAAGACCUUUAGUUGGAAGUCAUCCCUUACCUGCCAUCGUAGACUUCAUUCUGGAGAGAAACCUUACAAGUGUAAGGAGUGUGGCAAGACCUUCAAUCAGCAGUUAACCCUUAAACGCCAUCGUAGACUUCAUAGUGGAGAGAACCCUUACAAAUGUGAAGAUAGUGACAAAGCUUACAGUUUCAAAUCAAACCUUGAAAUACAUCAGAAAAUUCAUACUGAAGAGAAUCCUUACAAGUGUAAUGAGUGUGGCAAGACCUUCAGUCGGACGUCAUCCCUUACAUGCCAUCGUAGACUUCAUACCGGAGAGAAACCUUACAAAUGUGAAGAAUGUGACAAAGCUUUCCGUGUGAAAUCAAACCUUGAAGGACAUAGGAGAAUUCAUACUGGAGAGAAACCUUACAAGUGUAAUGAGUGUGGCAAGACCUUUAGUCGGAAGUCAUAUUUUAUAUGCCAUCAUAGACUUCAUACUGGAGAGAAACCUUAUAAGUGUAAUGAGUGUGGCAAGAACUUUAGUCAGAAGUCAUCCCUUAUAUGCCACCAUAGACUUCAUACUGGAGAGAAACCUUACAAGUGUAAUGAGUGUGGCAAGACCUUUAGUCAGAAGUCAAACCUUACAUGCCAUCGUAGACUUCAUACUGGAGAAAAACAAGUGUAAUGAAUGUGGUGAGGUUUUUAAUCAACAAGCACACCUUGCAGGUCAUCAUAGAAUUCAUACUGGGGAGAAACCUUAGAAAUGUGAAGCAUGUGAUAAAGUUUACAGUGGCAAAUCAAGCCUCAGAAGACAGGAGAAUUCAUACUGGAGAGAAAGCUUAUAAAUGUGAAGAAUGUCACAAAGUUUACAGUCGCACAUCAAACCGUGAAAGACAGGAGAAUUCAUACUGGAGAGAAACCAUAAAAAUGUAAGAGUUUGUGACAAGGCUUUUGGGCAUGAUUCGCACCUGGCACAACAUGCUAGAAUUCACACUGGAGAGAAACCUUACCAGUGUAAUGAGUGUGGCAAAGCCUUUAGUAGGCAGUCAACACUUGUUUACCGUCAGGCAAUCCAUGGUGUAGGGAAACUUUACUAAGGUAAUGAUUGUCACAAAGUCUUCAGUAAUGCUACAACCAUUGUGAAUCACUGGAGAAUCCAUAAGGAAGAGAGAUCAUACUAGGGUAAUAAAUGUGGCAGAUUUUUCAGACAUUGUUCAUACCUUGCAGUUCAUCGGUGAACUCAACGCUGGAGAGAAACCUUACAAAUGUCAUGACUGUGGCAAGGUCUUCAGUCAAGCUUCAUCCUAUGCAAAACAUAGGAGAAUUCAUACAGGAGAGAAACCUCACAUGUGUGAUGAUAGUGGCAAAGCCUUCACUUCACACCUCAUGAGACAUCAGAGAAUGCAUACUGGACAGAAAUCUUACAAAUGUCAUCAAUGUGCCAAGGUCUUCAGUCUGAGUUCACUCCUUGCAGAAUAUGAGAAAAUUCAUUUUGGAGGUAGUUGGUCCAUAUGCAAUGAGUAGAGCAAACCAUCAAGCAUUAAUUGACAUUAGGGUCAAUUCAGCAUUGACUUGAGUUUGUAUUGACUUAACAUUGAGUUCAAGCAUUAAUUGACAUUAGUGUUUAUGUUAAGAGGAUUGGGCCAGGCACAUCAGCUUACACCUGUAAUCUGAGCGCUUUGGGAGGCCAAGGUGGGUAGAUCACUUGAGGUCAGGAGUUUGAGAUCAGCCUGGCCAACAGACGUGAGCCAUUUUCCCAGCCUGUUUUUUGUUUCUUUAAAAAAACUGAUAGGGAUUUUUAUGGAUAUCAUGUUGAAUCUAAAUCACAUUGGGUUAUUAUAUAAUCAUUUCACAAUAUUAAUUUUUCCAAGCUAUCAAUAUGGGUUGUAGCUCAAUGUUUUUAAUCAUUUUGAUCAAUGUUUGUAGAUUUCAAGGUACAAACUUCUGACCUUUGUACGUUUAUUUCUAAGUAUUUCUUUAAGUUCUCCAGCAAAUGGAAGUGUUUUAAAAUUUUCUUUUAAAAUUGUUUAUUGUUAAAGUAUGGAAAUUCAACUAAUUUUUGGUGCUGAUACUGUAUUGUGCAAAUCCACUGACUAUGUUACUUAGUUCCAGUAGUAUUUUGGUUGGCUCUUUGUGAUUUUCUACACAGAAGAUUAUGUCAUCUACAAACAAAUAUAAUUUUACUUCUUACUUUCUGA